AGAUGGAGUCUCACCCUGUUCCCCAGGCUGGAGUGUGAUGGCACGAUCUUGUCUCACUGCAACCUCCGCCUCUCGGGCUCAAGUAAUUCUUUGCCUCAGCCUCCUGAGUGGCUGGGAUUACAGACGCACACCACCAUACCCGGCUAAUUUUUUGUAUCUUUAGUAGAGUCAGGGUUUCACUCAAAUUCCUGACCUCGUGAUCCUCCUGCCUUGGCCUCCCAAAGUGCUGGGAUUACAUGUGUGAGCCUCCGUGCCUAGCCAGUAACUGCAGAUCUUAAAACAGAUUUCCCCUCUUCUUCUUCUUCCUCUUCUUCCUCUUCUUCUUCCUCCUCUUCUUCUUCUUCCUCUUCUUCCUCUUCCUCCUCUUCCUCCUCUUCCUCUUCUUCUUCUUUCUUCUUUCUUCUUUCUUUUUCUUCUUUCUUCCUUCUUCUUCUUUCUUCUUUCUUUUUCUUUCUUCUUUCUUCCUUCUUUUUCUUUCUUCUUUCUUCUUCUUCGGAAUCUCACUCUUUGGCCAGGCUGGAGUGCAGUGGCACGAUCUCAGCUCACCGAAACCUCCACUCCCAGGUUCAAGUGAUUCUCCUGCUUCAGCCUCCCAAGUAGUUGGAAUUACAGGCAGCCACCACCAUGCCUGGCUAAUUUUUGUGUUUUUAGUAGAGACGGGGUUUCACUGUGUUGGCCAGGCUGGUCUUGAACUCCUGACCUUGUGAUCCACCUGCCUCGGCCUCCCAAAAUACUGGGAUUACAGGUGUGAGCCACUGCACCAGGCCUCCCCCUUUCUUAAGAUACAAGGAAGUGUAUCUUUUCAGUGUGUGCUCUUUAUGGAUGUAUACAAUGCAGAUGAAUUUAGGAAGGCAAUUUCAGAUUUUGAAAACUGUUGAAAUUAAACUUGAACAUUGAAAAAUCAAAUUUGCAGUUGUCUUAAGUGUUUGCAUUAGUUAGAUGCUUCACAAUUAAUAAAUACUAGCUAAUAUAAUUUUAUAAGACCCUUUGAAGAGGGAAUUGUGAGUUUAUUUUUAAGAUAAGCCAGGUUAUAUCAAAGAUAUUGUAACCAACUAGAUUUUAUUUGGAGACUUUGUACUCUGCUUUAGAAUCCAGUAGCUCUAUCAGUGUGAGCUGUUUCCAUUCUUGAGUAGAAGUUUUCUCCUGUUAUUUUUUCUUUGUUCUAGCUGGGUUUAAGACAGCCUUCUUUGUAGAAAUUGUUGGCCUGUUUAUCCUUCACCCACCCUGAAGACACUUAAUUUUAUGGACUGUUCUUGUACUGCCUCAUCACCAGAAAAAGCAGGCUGGAAAUUAACUGUCAUAUUCCCGCAGGUUUAAUUUAACUGAUUAUAAGAAAGUACAGUUAUUGUUCUACCUUCUUUAAAUCUUUGUCCUUGAUGACCAAGCUCAGGUUUUUAUUUUUGCUUAUUUAUUUAUUUUUUGGAAAUGGAGUCUCACUCUGUCACCCAGUCUGGAGUGCAGUGGUGCAGUCAUAGCUCGUUACAGCCUGGAACUCGCGGGCUUAAGUGAUCCUUCCACUUCAGCCUCCCAAGUAGCUGGGACUCCAGGCAUGUGCCACCACGCUCAGCUAAUUUUUAAAUUUUUUUGUAGAGAUAGGGUCUCGAUGUUACCCAGGUCUUGAACUUCUGACUCUGAGUGAUCUUUCCACCUCAGCCUCCCAAAGUGCUGGGAUUACAGAUAUGAGCCACCAGUCUGGGUGGGUUUUCUUUUUUAAAUAAUAGAUUUAAAUUGUUCAUUACUUUGUUUUGAACAUUUGUUGCACAAUGCCGGAGUAAUAUUUUGAUUAAAGUUUUUGAAUAUCAAGUUGAAAUUUCUAGAAAACAAAUUUCUGACUUGGAAUGUUUCCCUGAGAUAAUCGAUGGAUGACAUGUUAGAAAAAUGUUCUACUAUAUUAGGCAUUUAAAAAAUAACUGUAUAAUAUAGAGACUGUGGGAGCAACAAUGGUACAAAUUGCUGGUUGAGCAAAUUUUAAUUUUAGUUGCACACAGUAAAAUGUUCUUUGGUUUCAUUAAGAUUAACUCUUAUUUCCAUGUGAAUUAUUUUGGAUAUUAAUAGUGAGAUGCUUUAGCAUUGGAGAAAUUGCUUUAUAAAAACUGAAGGAUCAGACUUCACCUUAAGUGUAUGAAGUAGCUGCCAGACCUCAACAUUCGUGCCAUGAGAAUUUAAUUCUGAGAGCUUAAAUGCGUUAGUUUCAUUUUAUUUGCUUUGAAUGUUUUGUUUAUAUAUAGUUUUUUUUAGAGCCUCAUUUAAAAAAUAUAUGUAUUUCUAGUUUUUUUCUUCGAAUAUAUAAUACAGAUUUUUGGGAAAAUGUGGGUCAUGUUUGAAAAUUCUAUCGAUUGUAAAAAAAAAUUCCGACUCUUGGUUUUGGUUAAAUAAUUAGAACAGCUAUUUAGAAAAACUGAAAUAGUUAAUGGUUUUGGAGUUUGCAGGUGCCUGUUUUCUGAAAUAUUGAUUAUCUAUCCCUCGGGCAGAGUAUACGUAUUUGCCAAGUUUGUAUUUCUUUUUUCUAUUUCUUCAAAAUAAGUCCCGUUGAUUUUAAAAGAAUAAAGAGUUUCCCAGUAAGUACAAGUGUGGUACUUUUUCCCCCUCCACUUUGUACUUUAGUGUUAACCUUUAUUACAUAACCACAGAGAAUGAGGAAGAGAAUUGUACAAUGCAGAUAUUAAGCCUAUUGUUCUCCAAGGAAAGUCUUUGAUGUUAAGAGGUCCCUAAACCUCUUAAUUAUUUUAUUUACUUGUGAGAGGGGGUGCUUCCUUAAAUAUAUACGAGUCUUUUCUUAUAUUGCAUACACUUGCAACUAUUAUUUUGAAAUAAUAGUUGAGUGGUGUUUACAUUUAUGACCUGAUUCAUGUCUUUUGAAGUGCCACCACUGUUUCACCAUGGACUUGCUUACUCAGGUUGUUGGCAACAGCAUGGAAUUGCAUCAGAUCUUGCUGUAUUAAAUAAAUGAAGAUAUUAGAUGUCAGAAUUUUUAAGUAGUUCAUGGCUUUUGUUUUUAUUUUCUAUAUGAUCAGCUUCAUAGGGAAAGUUAUUUUUGAAACAAUUUGAGCUCCUAAUAAUUUUUUGAAGCUAUUUGUGUCUGGUCUUCCAAAGGCAAAAAUGGCCCAUUUUGACUCUGAUUUAGUAAUCUCCUUUGGCUUUAGUGGUUUUUAUCCUUCCUCCCACUAUCCUUUCCCCUCGUUUAGAGGUAGGAGGAGCCCAGUUCCAGUAUUUAAAAUGAAGAUCAAGAGUGGCAUAAUAGCUUCAUUAGGUGUUUUUCACCAAAAUAGGUCUGAAUAAGUCUGAAUUUGUGGUAGAAGGAACCAUAACAAAUUUGUUUAGUGCAUUACAGUUUUUGAGAAUAUGUUGUUUCACACACAUUGUUUCUAUAUGUUGUUUCCAUUUCAUGGUGAAAGCAUAAGGAAUCCAUUUAAAAAUAGAGUAAAAUGCUACAGCCAGUUGGGGGUUGGGGGCAGCCCCGUGGACCAGAAUUUGCCUCUGUGUGGGAAGUCAGCAGGACCAGAUGCCCCUCUCUUCUUUGGCUCUGUAGGUAUCUGGAUCUCUUAACAUAUAGAUGACAAGUUUUGGCCAGCUUUGAAAUUACAUUUGCUAGUGGAGGACACAUAUCAUUAACUCUGCAGUGGGAAUAAGGAAUUCAGUAGGUGCCUGACCCCAAAUGAUAAACUGCUAUUCUAAUUUUUAUGCUGUGUAAUAUAUUUUAGACUUUUUAAUAAAAAAGAUAAAAAUUGAGCAAUUUCAUGAAUUGUUAUGUUACAUCAAUUUACCAUAUGAAGAUUAAUUCAUGUUUUCAGAACAGUAAUACACAUUUCUGAAAUAUACAGAGACAGGUAAUAGUAUCAAAGGGCUUAAAAUAGAAUUUUAGUCUUCCUCGCCUCCACUCUCAGUCCUGCUGUCCACAGACAAUCUCUGUAGGCUCUAUUUAGCAUUCUCUCUCAUAUUUACCUGCAUAAUUCUAACCAAUGCUCUGUUAUUUCUUAAUUUGUCAUUUUUAGGUAUUAUUCCUUGAUAUCUUGCUGUGGUAAAUGAAGACUUCAGUGUUUGCACCACUUGCCCUUCAGUCUCUCCAUUUCCCAAUAUAAUUAGAUUACAUAUUUUGGUUACUAUAGUGAUUCAUUUUUCUUUCUUGUCCAACAUUUUAUUUUUUCUUGAGUCAAUAAUUGCCUCUUUUAAAAAUUGCUUAGUUUACCUUAGACACAUUUUCUCUUAAAUGUUCCUUUAAACCUGUCAAAGGUCUGUGAAUAUUAUUUUUUAACCCAUUCAACGGAUUAGAUAAUCUCCAAGCACUAACUCUUUUCUAAAAUCCUUUCCAGAGCCCUCUGACCUCUGCUGUCAUUUGAAAUAGUUCUCCAGGCUGGACAGUUUUUAUCGUGUGAUUCCCUCUGUUGUUCUCUUAUAAUAUUAGAUCCCUUAUUUCUUGGAUCCCAUGUCUUGUUUUUCUUGGUUUAUUUCAUUGUUUUGCUGGAGUACAUCAAGCUCCUUUCUCACAGGAGGUAAUUUUUUUUUCUCUAAUUGCAUGGCACAUUAAGGGAGGUAAAUUUUUGAGCCUUUGCAAGUCUGACAUUUUUAUUUUACCUUUAUACUUGAUUGCUUGGCUGAAUAGAAAAUAUUAGUAAGAAAAUAAUUUUCCUUUAGAGUUUUAAAGGCAUUGUUGGUUUGUUUCUAGGCUCCCAGAGUUGCUGUUGAGAAACCUGAUGCCUUCCUGAUUUCCUCCUCCACAUAUGUCCUUUUAUUCUUUUUCCUAUAAUUCUUUAAGGUAUUCUUUUCAUCCUCUGUAUUCUGAAAUUUCAAAAUAUGGCUGGGCAUGGGUAGUUUUUUUUUUAUUUUAUUUUUAAUAGGAAGUGAAGGGAUUUUUUUAUGUAUAGGUUCACAUCCUUGAGUUAAAAGACAUUUUUUUGUACUAUAAAUUUGAUAGUGUGCUCCUCCCCCCAUACUUAUAUCCCCCAAUUUAUUCUUUUUUUUCUUUCUGGAACUCUUAUUAGUUGGAUGUUGGGUGUCCUGAGUGUAGUCUCUGAUUUUCUUAUUUCUUUGCCUUUUGGUUCUAGUUUCUGGUAUAUUUCCUUGAUUUUUUUUUUUAUUAUAUUAUACUUUAAGUUUUAGGGUACAUGUGCACAAUGUGCAGGUAAGUUAUAUAUGUAUACAUGUGCCAUGUUGGUGUGCUGCACCCAUUAACUCGUCAUUAGGCUUAUUUAACAUUAGGUAUAUCUCCUAAUGCUAUCCCUCCCCACUCCCCCCAAUUUCCUUGAUAUUUUUUCUUCCAUUCCUUCUGUUGAAUUUUGAUCAUUGUAUUUAAAAAUUUUAAGAGCUCUUUCUCAUUUCCCAAUCAUUCCUUUUUCACAUAUCCUCUUGCUAUUGUUUUGCAGUAUCUUCUCUUACCACUCCAGCAGUUCAGAGUAUGUUGGUUUUGAAGUUUUGCUGUGCUCCCUGUAUGGUUUCUAUUUCUCCUGGGUUCCUCUUUUUCUUUUUAAAAUGAUUCUUUCAGAUUGGAGGUUUUCUAUAAAGAUCUGUUUUGUCUUUGUCUUUUCAUAUAACAGUGAACUUUUUCAUGUAAAAAGCUUUGUAACUGGGUGGGGCUUGUCCACAGUGGGCUUCACUGUGAGGUGGGGAGCAAGUCACCUUCAUUGGAGGAAGACACUCAUAUCUGUGCUGAGAAUUUUUUCUGGUACCAUUGAGUUUUUCGGUUUUCCCUCUGGGAGGUGGGCACCUGGCCACUGAUGUUCUGAGAUCAGAUUGCAGAAGUUCCAUGACUCAGUUGUCCUUAGAGUCCCUAGUCUCCUUGUGUUCAGUCCUGUCCUUACCUGCUGUCUGCUGUGUCCCUAUACCUAGAGCUCCUCCCAUCUGCAUUCUUCCUGGCUGACACUCAGGCCAUAGCUUCCUCUGCACUACUAAGAUUGUUAUUGCUCCCCUAACUUCUUUCUCACUUACAAAAAGCUGUUGAAAUCUUUUGUCUGCUUUGGUUACCUCACACUGUUCUCUUUAUCUUUGUGGGUUUGUAUCUGUUUUUUUCCUUUAUUGUCAUUUAAGUGGGUCUUAGGUGGGAGAAGAGCUAAGUAGAAUUUGCCACGUUUAGUUUAGUGUCCAUUUUUAAAUGUAUAUCAUUUGUAAUCCUGUUUUUAGGGCACAGUGUUUUGCCCUAUCAGAAAUGGAUCUUAUUAGUUACUCAGAGUUAAAUCAUUGAACUGAAAUUUUACAUUAAUCUAUUUGAAUAAAAAUUUAUAUUCAGAUUUACCUUCUCUGAUAAAUAGAACAAAAUAUUGUUGCUGUUAUCAGAGUCAGCAGAGAAAAUAGGCAAGCCAGGGGGUUCGACCUUGCUUGGAAAGUCAGAUCACAAGCCAGGCUUUGGAUAGGUAUAUGCCUGUGAAAGAAAGUUGUAAGGUCAUUGGGACUACUGCAGUUAAUGCAUUGUAAUACUUUUAUUGGACUAGCUCAUCAUUCAUUAAUGAAGGCAAGUUAGUGCCAGGUUUAUAGGAUUUUUGGCUCUGUACAUUGGUAAUUUAACCUUCUCCCUUGUGUUUUAGUUUUUAAAAAGUAUGAUCUUAAUUGGAAGUAAAGGACACAGAUUUUUAAUCUCAGAAUUUAAAAAGACUUUUGAUUUUGAUAUAAUUUUAUACUCAGAGAAACACUGCUAAGAAUAGUACAUACAAAGAACUUCCGUAUACUUAGAUUUGCCAGUCGUUCACAUUUUGCCUCAUUUGUUUUAUCAUGUAUAUAUUUACUCUCUGUUUAUAUAUUUCCCCUUAUUAAUUUACAGAUAUAACACUCCUUUAUCCAUAGUUUUGUUUUUCCCCAAGAACAGGUCUCUUUUUUUUUUGGGACGGAGUCUUGCUCCGUUGCCCAGGCUGGAGUGCAGUGGCGUGAUCUCGGCUCACUGCAAGCUCCGCCUCCCAGGUUCACAGCAUUCUCCUGCCUCAGCCUCCUGAGUAGCUGGGACUACUGGCACUCACCACCACGCCCGGCUAAUUUUUUGUAUUUUUAGUAGAUAUGGGGUUUCACCGUGUUAACCAGGAUGGUCUGGAUCUCUUGACCUCAUGAUCUGCCCGCCUCAGCAUCCCAAAGUGCUGGGAUUACAAGCGUGAGCCACCGCGCCUGGCCGGGUCUUUCUUUUCAAUCAGCAGAGAAUAUUGGUCAAAUCAGGACAGUUGAUACUGAUAGAAUGCUGUUACCUAAUGCACAUUCCAUGUUCAGAUUUCCUCAAUUGUCCCAACAAUGGCCUUCAUAGCUAUUACUCCUUUCUGUUUACCUCCCCAGCCACCCUGGAUCUAAUCCAGGAUCAUGUGUUAUAUUUAGUUGUCAUAGCUCUUUAGUUUUCUUUCAUCUCCAAUAGUUCCUCAGCCUUUGUUUUUCAUGUCUUGGCUUUUGGCUUUUUUUUUUUCUAUUCUAACAUCAUAAUGUCUUGUUAUUUUUGAAGAGUUCAUUUCAGUUAUUUUAUAAAAUGUUCUUCAGUUUGAGUUUUCAGAGGUUUCUUCAUGGUUAGAUUCAGGUAAUGCAUUUUUGGUAGGAAUACCACAAAAGUAAUGUUGUGUCUUCUCAGGCAUCAUAUCAAGAGUUGGUCUGUCUUGUUUUUGGUGAUACUAACUUUGAUUACUUUAUUAAGGUAAUAUUUGGUAGGUUAAUCAGCUAUAAAGUUACUAUUUUCUCCUUUGCUAUUAAGAAGUAAUUUGUGGGAAAUGUUUUUAGAUUAUGUAUAUACCUCGUUUCUUACCAAAGUUUUACCCAGUAGUUUCACAUCCAUUGAUGAUUCUUGCCUGAAUCAGUUAUUAGUAGGAUGAUUGCAAGGUGAUGAUUUUCUGACUCGUAAUUCUUUUACAUGUUAGUUGGCAUUCUGCUAUAAGAAAGAACUUUCUCCCCUGCUUACUAUUAAUUUGCUUACUUAUCUUAAUAAGCACUCGGUUUUUUUUUAUUCUAAGGUACUCAUCAUUAUUUAUUUUGAGGCUCAAAUUAGCUUAUAUUUAGCUGGUGGGAGCACCCUUAAGCUGUGAUUUGGGCACGCGCCGUCAUUCUUUGAGCCCUUUUUACUUUCUCGCACAAGAUGUUCCAGGCUCAUCUUGUACUUAGCCUGUUGCAGCCUUGGAAUUAGCCAUUUCUCCAAGUAGCCCUCAUUCUUUUUGGCUGGGAAUAAUGUUUAUAAACUAAGAUCUCUCAGCACAGUAGAGCUGAGAAAUAUAAAUAAAUAAGCAUAUCUACAUCUGUUUAUGUCUGUGUGUAUUUGUGUGUUUAUCACCAUGAUUUUAUACUGAUACCUACAAUUUCAUUCAACACCACAAGCCUAGUCUUGCCCCUUUCCAUAUUUGUAACACCUUUCUCCAACAGUAAGAACUGGUUCCCAUUAUCUACAAUGAGUGUGUACUCAUUUGCACAAUUCUAUAAUCAGAGAAAAUAGUUCCAGAAUUGCUAACCCAUACCAUUGUAAAGAAAACCCCUUAUAACUCAAGUUCAAAUUUGUUUACAGUUCUUUUUGUCUGUAUACUGAAAACAUAAAAAGUACUAUGUUAAAAAGCUAUUUGGUUUAGUUUUAGUCUCCCUUUUAAUACACUUAUUUAACAUAAAGUUUGUUCAUUUGUUUGUUUGAUUUCUGUUUUAGAUUUUUUUUUUUUUUUUUUUUUUUUUUUGAGAUGGAGUUUUGCUCUUGUCCCCAGGCCGGAGUGCAAUGAUGCAAUCUCGGCUCACUGCAGCCUCCGCCUCCCAGGUUCAAUCGAUUCUCCUGCCUCAGCCUCCCGAGUGGCUGGGAUUACAGGCGUGGGCCACCAUGUCCGGCCAAUUUUUGUAUUUUUAGUAGAGACAGGGUUUCACCAUGUUGGCAGGCUGGUCUUGAACUCCUGACCUCAAGUGAUCUGCUCACCUUGGCCUCCCAAAGUGCUAGGAUUACAGGCAUGAGCCACCAUGCCUGGCCCCAUUUUAAGAUUUUUAAAAUCUCAUCCUUACUGAUUUUAUUUUGCUUUUUGAGUAUAUAAAACAUUAUCAUGGUUCCAAAAGUUAAAACUACACAAAAAGCUGUGCUAAGCAAUGUCACUACCUAAUGCCGGCCGCUCACUCCUACCCACCCCCUGUAGACAACCAAUUUCAUUAAUUUCUGAUUGAUCUUUCCUGUGUUUCUUUUUGUAAAGAAAAGCAGGUGGGUAUUUUCUUUUUUUCCCUCACAAAAGAUAGCAAACUAGAUACAUUCUUUUGGACUUUUUUUUUUUUUCAUUUAGCUGUAUAUCCUGGAUGUCACUCCAUGUUUGUAGGAAUUUUCCUUAUUCUCUUUUUUAAAACAGCUUCUAGUACUCCAUCUGUGGAUGUGCGACAGUGAAUUCAACCCAUCUCCUAUAUGUGGGCAUUUAGGUUGUUUCCAAUAUUUGUAGUUACAAAUAAUGCAGCAGUUAAUACCCUUGUACAAAGAUAUUUUUGUAUUAUCAGGUAUCUUCAGGGAAGAACACACAAAAAAAUUAACUUUUUAAUUGUGUGAGCAGCAAUAUGUAAGAUAAUACUUCAAGCUAUUUGUCUGCCUACUCCACACUUCCACUGUGGUCUUAGAAAUGUAUCCAAGGCUGUUGAAGUGAAAUACUUAUCUAUCGUAAUUAUUUUUCUGUUGGGAAACCUUGAAAUUAGAGAGCUGGAAGUAGCCUUGGGGACAUUUUUAGUCAAGUAGUAGCCGAUCAUAGGCCCUGGGUCAGGGUUCAUUUUAAGCAGUUAACUGUUCCUUGUACACACUCAUCAGUGCUUUUCUGUCAGCUCGGCUCAGACCAGCUGUUUCGGAUACUUCUCUCUUCCAUUUAAUUUAAUUCACAAGAGGUUCCUUCAUGUUGAACUGUUGAGUGGCCACUCCCUGGAGUUAUAGAAUGGCAGUAGGACAAGACAAUUAUACAUGGGAUAGAAAUAAGGAUUUCAGCAUCUGUUUUCUCUGAUAGGCCUCAGAGGAUUGAUGGUUAUGAACUGUAGAUCGUCAGAGGAAUGGCAUCUUGGAUUCCCAGAUGCUGCUGCUGGUCUCCUCCGGUGAUUUGUUUAUUUGAGACAAAAUCUUGCUUUGUUGCCCAGGCUGGAGUGCAGUGGCGCUAUCUUAGCUCACAGCAGCCCUUACCUUCCACGCUCAAGUUAUUUUCCCGUUGUAGAGGCGAGGUCUCACUAUAUUGCCCAGGCUGAUCUGGAACUCCUGGUCUCAGGCGAUCCUCCUGCCUUGGCCUCCCAAAGUGUUGGGAUUACAGGCAUGAGCCACUGUGCCCAGUCCUCUCAGGCGAUUAAUGACUUCUAGUCUUUUGUUCCAGCUAGUGAACAUUGGAGUAGAAGGGAGACGUCCUCCUGCAUUGCUAGAUAACCACGUAAAAGGUUGGCUAGCAUAGCUUCCCAUCAGAGGGGCCACAAGUGGAUUACAUAUGUGUUGAAAUAAAUGAUCCCCUCAGCCUAGAGGUGGCUGUGCUCCCAGACAAAUCAUUUCUGGCUGUGAGAAGCCUCUUCAGUUAAUGUGCAUGUGUCAUACAGAUAUUUUCUAUGCGUGCCCUGACAUGGGAAAGGUUGGGAAAGUAGGCUAAAGCACAGUCUCAAAAUUAGCCUCUAAGGAUGUUGCUAAACCAAGGAUAUUGCUCCUUAAAGAGAACCAGGUAAUAGAGUGAAGAGGAAUUGAAUUAUUUAGGGUAGAGGUUAAAACCUACUUGUCCAUAAAGAUAAGCUGAUAACCAUAUCUUAAAUCUGGUGUGAUAUGAAAUUCUUACUCACUUCUUUGCUAAAACAAAGUUAGAAAUUAAAAUGUAUUUCUAAGUGACUUGGCUUGUAACCCCAUUUUAUUGGAUAUUGGAAUAUAGAACAGUUCACAUUAAAGAACUUAGCAUCUUUGUUCAUUUGAAUUUUGACAUUUUAUUCAUUGCUAUACUGAUAAUGUACUGGCAGUGCACUAAAUGAAGUAGAUACCAAGGGUAUAUUAUGGUUGAUGAGAUUAGUGAACCAGGAUUUAAUGUCUUUUCUGAAUACUUCUGAGUUUGAUGUAUUCUAAUAAAGUUUUGACACUUGAGUUGCUUCUGUACUUAAAUGUUUUACCUGAGUGGCAUUCUAUUAUCUAAACCUUAUCUGUUAAAAUGUGCUUCUAAAAUGCAUUUUUCCUGAAGUAUUUUACAUUAGAUACGUAAAAUUUAAUGAUUCUGACAUUUAAGGUGGUUAUAACAGUUACAUCAAUUUUGAAAUAAGCUUAUUAAAAUUGAGUAUUUGGUGUUUUGAAUAUAAUUUAAUUUAAUUCUGGUGUAGGAGGAUUUUGAGGGAAUGGAACUGACAUUCACUGAGUGCUUUCCGUUGAUUAGGCCCUGUGCUGUGUGCACUUUAUGUAGUUUAUCUCAUGAAAUCUUUACCAUAGCCAUGUGAGGUAGAAGGUGGGAUUUGACCCAUUUCACAGAGAGGAGGCAGGCUCUGGAACGAACUUAGCGUAAGGUCAUAGAAUAAAAUAGUAGAGCUACAACUUUAAGACAGUUGGUUCUGAAGCCCGUGCUUGAUACAAGUCACAUGACCUGUAUCAUAUUUAUUUUGAGUCUGCAGUGGAACAAAUUCCUACAAAGGCAACUCAUUCUGUUUGGUACAUUUUUGUAUAAAAGAGGGAAGGAAUUCUUCUCGAAGGGUUCAAGGGCAGGUGAUAAAGGAAUUUGGCUAGUUCAGCUAAAACAAUGUGGAGCAGAGUUUCCUGGUCACUGUGCCCCUUCCUUUUUAGGUCAGUUGUGGAACAAUUUGCUAGGAAUUUUGUGAGAAAAUUGUGAGUAGUUCCAGCUUACAAAGGCCUGGGAUCAGGCAUUGCUGGGCAUGAUGGGGAUCAAGUCAUGCUGGCUGAGGAAUAUGUCAGAACUCUUGGGGUAAAGAGAAAUAGAAGCAGAAUGAGUAAUGUUCUCAAGUCUUGUAAUUAUUUAGAAGCAUUUUUCCAAGUUCAACCUUCAGUAAAGCCUGGGGUUUCCUAGAAUGCUUAUUAAGUAACAUAAUCCAAAGAAGCAAAAGGAAGGAAGGAUAAGGAUUUGUGCCUUUUAAUGAAGACAAAAGGAAUUUCUGCCACUGUUUAUGGCACUUUCUUAAGAAUCUUUACCUAGAAUUUGGGAUUUCUAUGGAAAUAGUGCUUUUGAAAAUUUGAAGGUUUUAAACUUACUUGUUACUGAGUUAUUGUUAGGAAUGAUGUUUGUGCUCAAGAAUUAGGUUGUCCUGAGAUAGAGGUGGCACAUCUAGAUUUGAGUUAUUAAAAUAUUGAUGUGAUACACAAAGAUUUAGUCCAAAGGACAGUGGCAGCUUAGUUGAAGAUAAAUAUCAAGUCUUUACUCUCACUACUUCUGUUGUAGAGGGAGUAGUAUAGUCAUUGGAUAGCUUUGAAUCCUACUGGGUAAAACCUUCUGAAGUUUCUUUUGCAUCCUCACUUUUCCUAAACAACAGGUCAGUCAUUCCAGUGAGUUGUUUGGUGGGUGUGGAUGAUGCUGCAUCACUGAUACUGCUCCCUCUGUUAAGUGGUGGUCUGGUUAUCUGUUGCUGCAUGACAAACAGCCAUACAUCCUAGAAGCCUAAAGCAACCAUUUCAUUUUGCUUAUAAUUUUGUGGGCCAAGAAUUCAGGAAGAACUUGCCUGGGAUUGCAUCAGGUGGAGAACGUGGACUCACAGAGUUACCAGACGUGUGUUAAGAAGACACUUUGGAGGAGGAUGUUCUGGAGUCUUCUUAACUCACCUGUCUGGUACCUCUGUGCUCCUUGGUGUCUCUCUGUCCCCCAGUGGUGUCAUAAUCUCCCCAGUCUCCCUGCACAUGGUUUGGGCUUCUCUCAGCAUGUUGGUCUCUGGGUAAUUAGACUUCUUACAUGGCGGCUGGCUCUCCCAAGAGCAAGCAUUUCAAGCAAUAGCAAGAGGGAGCUGUGGAUUUCAUAAGGCCUGGAGUUGCAGGUUGACAUAGAAUCACUUCUGCCAUAUUCAGUGCGUUGGGGCAGUCACAGAGCCUGCCCAGAUUCGGAGAAUGAGGACAUAGACCCUGUCUCUCCAUGGGAAGAAUGUCAAAGAAUUUGUGGCCAUCUUUAAUCUACCACAAGGCCAUUAAGCAAAAAGGAGAGGGUUGUUACAAGAAAUGCUGAACUGACUUUACCAGCAAAUGUAAGCCUACUUUAUAUAAUGAUUCAGAAGAGACUGAUUGUCAGGAAUAAGAAAGGGAUAGAGGCAAAAGAGAGCCCCCAGAAGGAGGAAAGUGGAAAAAUUUUUCAUGGGAAAGUGGAAAGGCAACCAAGAUAAACUUUGCUUCAUAAUUUUAUCUUUCCUGCCUUGGACCUGAAUUCAGUCUUGGUUCUGUGAUCUUGCCCUUGAGUCCCAGGUGGCCACUUCUGACCACUUUGGAUUUGGUGCUCAUGCCUGGUCUCCUCCCCAGUAUCAGGACCUCUGGUUGGCUUCCCAAGCUCUAUAUUGGUCACCCCUUUGACCCUAAGUAUCUCCUGUUGCCCUUUAUGAGAACUCUCCUGUUGCCCUGUUCCCUGGGAACCUAACCAUCCUCUUUCAGAAUGAGCAGCAUUGUUGGGGCUGGGGAGACAUCAGACACUGAUUUUGGCUGCCCUCGGACUGCCUGGGCACCUUGGCAGUUGCUUCAUGUAGCUUGAUUCCUUCUUUUCUGGAUUACAUUAUGGCUCAGUUCUUGCUCUCUUUUUGUGACUUUACCAACUCCUCCCCCUAAUAAUUUCAAGGGACUCAAGUUAUAGAUAGAAGAGACUUCUGAAAUUUCAGCAUAGAAUAGGCUUGUGAACAUGCAGUUCAGAGAGGAUUUAUAGUGUACAGAAGAUUUUAUGUCUUGCUUUUAAGCAUCUAAAAAUGUUUCAUUUGGAAGGUAAGUUAGGUCCGUCUGGAAUAUAUUUUUACUUAUAUGUACUGGAAUGUUUAUAGAAUUUUUAUGAUGAUACUGCCCUAUCCUCCAGUUUUAAGAGGAAUAACAGUUUUACUAUUGAUACUUUCACGAUGUAUGUGUGUGUUUUAAUAACUGCUGCAAAAUUUCAAAAUUUUCAUUGAUUAUAAUUUUACAAAUCCAUAGAGCUAUAAUCUUGGAUUUUGAUUUAACUUUCCACUCAUGCUUGAAAAUUUAGAAUAAGUUCAUUUUAUUAGGACUUUAUAAUACCAGUAUCUUUAAAUUUAAAACACUUUAAAUUUAAUUUUUAUUAUAAAAGAAAUAAUGCUGUUUGAAAAACUUUUAACAGUAUAGUGGCUCCUAUCCCCAUGUUAUUCCUUUUACAUAGCUGAUAACAGCUACUUCCAGUCUUUAAAAAAUUUAUAUGCCGGUAUGUAGUACAUACAUAGACUCAGAAACACAUAGCAUGUUAUCUUUUUAAAACAAAAGUUUUAGUUUCCUGGACGACUGCUUUGCAACAGUCAGUGCCUUGAAACACUCUAUGAGUUUAAUUUCCAGCCCUAUCACUUAGUAAUUUAGCAAGUUACAGUACUGCUCUGUGCCUCAGUUUCCUCUUCUGUAAAACAGACCAAAUGAUGGUCUGUACCUCAUUGGAUUGUAGAAGAUUAAUUAGCACCUGUAUAUAGCACACAGUAUGUACUAUAUAAAUGUUAACUAAAUGAAAAUGAACUUGCUUAAAAAACAUAUCCUAGAUGUUUCCUUAUGGGUUGCUAAUAUUUUUAGAGUGUUGCACUUUAAAAAUUGUGUAGGCGGGUGGUUCUUGAGUUUCACUGUUGUAGCAGCAUGUUUGUCUGUAAUGAUCUUGAACAGUGAUUCCACAUACUUCCCACACCCUUGUUGCAGUGAGUUGCUGUUACUGAUGGGCAAUGUGUUUGUGUCUCAGGGAUGAUGGGAGGCAAGAAAAAACUUGAAAACCAUUGGUUUAGAAAAUUAUACUACAUUAGCAGUUAAUCUUUUUGUUAAGCCUUUUAAGAGACUUAGGCAGAAAGUAGAGUUGGAAGGAUUUUAUUUAUGGGGGAUGAUGAUAUGAUUGUUUCAUCUAACUUUUGCCAGUCCUUAUGUUCUUUAAAUUAUUUUACUUUGAGACAGGGUCUUGCUUUGUCGCCCAGACUGGAGUGCAGUGGUGUGAUCUCGACUCACUGCAGCCUUGACUUCCUGGGCUCACGGGAUUCUCCCGCCUCAGCCUCCGGAGCAGCAGGGACCACAGGUGUGCACCACCAUGCCCGCCUAAUCUUUUUUUAUUUUUAGUAGAUAUGGGGUUUCCCUGUGUUGCCCGGGCUGGUCUUGAACUCCUGGGCUCAAGCAAUCCUCCCACCUUGGCCUCCCAAAGUGCUGGGAUUACAGGUGUGAGCCACUGUGCCCAGCAUGUUCUUUGAAUAAUUUUAUAAUUUAGAGGGGACAUGAUCAUCACCUACUCUUCAUUUUACACUAAGGAAAUAGACCCAGAAUGGUAGUGAUGUUCUCUCUUCUGUAGCUAGUAAUGGUAGAGCCAGAACUAGAAUCCCGGUCAUCUGAUCCUCAUCUUUCUGAAUUCUUGAGAAGAAAAAGAGCCUUCUCUCCCAGUUGAAACAGCUGUGAAUAAUGGAUGCACUAUAAAUGGCUUACCUGUCAGUGCCAUGUGCUUAAACUAUUCUGUGUAGAGACAGUGAUGAAGUUGUGUCAUAAGCGGUCAUGUAUGAUGUUUUGUCCAAAAAUUUAGAAUUCCAGACUUGUUGGUAGGCCUCGAAUAUCAAAUAUCCUCUAUUAUGAGAUUCUCUGUAUGCAUACUAACAGGAUAUUGAAGAUCAGUGGCUAUGUAGAAAUAACAUAUUCAGUGUGGAUGUGCUUUUGUUUUAAGAACUCCUUUUCUUGUGAACACAACCUGAAAAGAUGCAUGGAUUAAUUAGGCCUCUAUAGGCACAGAACUCCCUGGUUUCUGCUCCGGUCUCUCUUGAUAAAGGGCCAUCUGCCCUUCCGUAUAGCACGGACUAAACCACUUUUGGCCUCUAGGUCACUUAGAUGCCUUUGUGUGCCUUCGGUUCUCAUCUGGUUUUCAGGAGAGUUAAAUGUUUAAGUGGUUUUAGGAGGAAGACUUGAGUCUGAGACAUGUUUUAGAGGCUGGGGCUCUUCCCACCCUCUCCAUGGCCCAGCAUAUGUGAUAGCUUCUACCUUCUGGAGAAUGGCUCUAGCUCAGGAGAGGAUAGAGCUUCUUCAUCUCCUCCAUGCAAAGGAGCCCUCCUGCCAUCUUGAAGAGCUUGAGGCUGAGGUGAGAACAGGGACAGAGGAAGAUUCUGAAGCCGUAGCUGAAGAGGAGGCAGUGAAAGGAGCCUAGGCUUUACAGACGACCCUGGAAACCUUUAAUACUGUUUCCAUGGGAAAUGUGUUUAUCCUGCAGCCUUCAAAUGUUUAUCUGGUGUGACUGUAUUAUGCCCUCAGAGAGUACUGUAUGUUGCCCAGGCUGGCCUCGAACUCUAGGCUCAAGUGAUUCUUCUGCCUCAGCCUCCCAAGUAGCUGGGACUACAGAUGCAAUCACCACCACACUUGGCAGUGUGCCGGUCCAACAAAAGCCCUUGGGUCUGUUUGACUUGUUCAAGUGUCCACUGUGGAAGGUAUGUGAAUGGCCAUGCAAAAAAACAUUAUGAAGAUGCACAAGUACCUUUAACCAACCAUAAGAAAUCAGAAAAGCAAGAUAAAGUUCAGCACACAGUAUGUAUGGAUUGCAGUAGCUACAGUACAUACUGUUAUCGCUGUGAUGAUUUUGUGGUUAAUGACACCAAGCUGGGACUGGUACAGAAAGUCAGAGAACACUUACAGAACUUGGAAAACUCAGCUUUCACAGCUGACAGGCAUAAGAAAAGAAAACUUUUGGAAAACUCAACACUAAACAGCAAGUUAUUAAAAGUAAAUGGAAGCACCACUGCCAUUUGUGCCACAGGCCUUCGGAAUUUGGGGAACACAUGUUUCAUGAAUGCCAUCCUUCAGUCACUCAGUAACAUUGAGCAGUUUUGCUGUUAUUUCAAAGAACUGCCCGCCGUGGAGUUAAGGAAUGGGAAAACAGCAGGAAGGCGGACAUACCACACCAGGAGCCAAGGGGAUAACAAUGUGUCUUUGGUAGAAGAGUUUAGAAAGACACUCUGUGCUUUAUGGCAAGGCAGCCAGACUGCAUUUAGCCCAGAGUCCUUAUUUUAUGUUGUUUGGAAGAUUAUGCCAAACUUUAGGGGCUAUCAACAGCAGGACGCCCAUGAAUUCAUGCGCUACCUUUUGGACCACCUACACUUGGAACUUCAGGGCGGUUUCAACGGUGUUUCCCGCUCAGCAAUUCUGCAGGAGAAUUCUACUCUGUCUGCAAGUAACAAGUGUUGCAUAAAUGGAGCAUCUACUGUUGUCACGGCUAUAUUCGGAGGCAUUCUCCAAAAUGAGGUUAACUGCCUCAUAUGUGGGACAGAAUCUAGAAAGUUUGAUCCAUUCCUAGACCUUUCAUUAGAUAUUCCAAGUCAGUUCAGAAGUAAGCGCUCUAAGAAUCAAGAAAAUGGACCAGUUUGUUCGUUACGAGAUUGUCUUCGCAGUUUUACCGACUUAGAAGAACUUGAUGAGACAGAGUUAUAUAUGUGCCAUAAAUGCAAAAAGAAACAAAAGUCCACAAAAAAGUUUUGGAUUCAAAAACUACCCAAGGUGCUAUGCUUACAUUUGAAAAGAUUUCAUUGGACAGCAUAUUUAAGAAAUAAAGUUGAUACAUACGUAGAAUUUCCACUGAGAGGCCUAGACAUGAAAUGCUACUUACUAGAGCCUGAGAACAGUGGCCCGGAGAGCUGCCUGUAUGACCUCGCCGCUGUGGUGGUGCACCAUGGUUCCGGGGUUGGUUCUGGACAUUACACAGCAUACGCAACUCACGAAGGCCGCUGGUUCCACUUCAAUGACAGUACUGUAACACUGACUGACGAGGAGACUGUGGUGAAGGCGAAGGCCUACAUCCUUUUCUACGUGGAACACCAGGCCAAAGCUGGAUCGGAUAAACUUUAAUACCUCCUCCAAAUCAUCAUUCACCAACCAUACCAGAGAAACAUUUCCAGUUUUCCACAAAUACUUGAUACAAGAUUUAAUUUCAUUAUGCACUUUUCAAUUUCCUAUUUUGGAUUUAGUUUUGUCAAUGGUAGUGACUUACUGAACAUGGGCACCAACUAAUUUUGUUGUUGUUCUACCAGAAAACCUCAGCAGAUGUUUUGAUUUGCUGCUUUAGUUGUAAUAAUUCAAUUUUUAUAGGUAGUUGUAAGAACUUAGUCUUAUUUGACUUUUUUAUUUUAUGUUAAUGUUUUCAGUUCUCACUUUGAGGCACAUUUACAUCAAUGCUUUUGUUCCUCUCACAUGCUGAAAGCAAGAUGUGUUCCUUAUUGUGAAGAGCGACACAACUGCCUGCUGCCUUUCCACAGCUAUAAUGGACAUCAGGUUGACUCUAAAUCAAGGAUCAUGUGUGCACAAUACUUGUGGCCCACAAAAUUUCACAAUGACUGCUGAGGAAUCAUUCUUUUUGCCUGUAAAAUAUAACAAAGGGCAUCAUUAAGUAGACCAGGUAAUUACUGCUUGUCUCUCAAGGCUGCUGUCUUUAUCAGCACUAACUAAAUAAAUUUGUUGGUUCAGUUGUACUUGUCCUGCAAAUACAAGAAUUACUCUCUUUGUUGGUUUUUUUGGUUUUGGGGCAUACUUGUUUGCGGGGAGGUAAGAUGGGAGUAAAGACCAAAUACAUGUAAUGUUUAAAAAAAAUGCUGUGACUCACUGACAUGGUAUAGGUGUUACCAGUGAGGUAAAGCCAUGGCGUCUGCCUCCUUUUGAAUCAGUAUCUCAUUCCCCCUUAGUUGUACCACUGGAAGUCACGACAUGUCCAUUAUAGACUUACUUACUGCUUGUGUUUGGCAUCUGAGUCUGAGGUGUGACCCUCUGGGAUUUACUUGGAUCAUCACCCGCACUUCAGUUUAUCACUGGGGGGUGUGCUUCCACAGGAGGAAAUUUAGAAUCUUCGCUGCUCUGGGUUUUAACACCUCUCUCUGGCCUAUCCUGAUUGAUAGGACAAGUUGAAAAUACUGUUGGAGUAAGUAAGUGGAGUUUUCGUUUUGUUUUUUGGGGGUUUUUGGAGACAAGAGUCUCUCUCUGUUGCCCAGGCUGGAGUGCAGUGGCACGAUCUCAGCUCAUUGCAACCUCGGCCUCCCGAGUAGCAAUUCUCCUGCCUCAACCUCCUGAGUAGCUGGGAUUACAGGUGCCCACCACUACACCUGGCUAAUUUUUUUUUUGUAUUUUUAGUAAAGACGGGGGUUUACCAUGUUGGCUAGGGUGGUCUCAACCUCCCUCCUGACCUCAGGUGAUCCGCCUGCCUCAGCCUCCCAAAGUGCUGAGAUUACAGGCGUGAGCCAUCACGCCCAGACAGUUUUGUUUUUAAAAAACAGAUUUAACUCAAAGAUUCAAAUUUGGAACCAGAAUCCCAUUUAAAGAAAGCAGUUGUGGUUUCUACAAGUGUUCUAAGACAGUCCUGUGGUGGUUUUUUUUUUUUCUUUUUUUUGGUUGGGGGCGGUGGGGGUUGGUAGACAUAGCCUACCAAUUCUCCACAAGGGACAAAAUGUAUCUUGUGUUAAGCCAACGAGACUUUCUGGCAAUUUUUUUUUUUUUUUUUUAAUGGAGUCUUACUCUGUCCCUCAGGCUGGAGUGCAGUGUGGCAUGAUCACAGCUCACUGUAGCCUCAACCUCCCAGGCUCAAGCGAUCCUCCCACUUCAGCCUCGAAGUAGCUGGCACCACCACACCCAGCUAAUUUUUAAUAUUUUUACUAGAGAUGGGGUUUCACCACGUUGCCCAGGCUGGUCUUGCACUCCUGGGCUCAAGUGAUCCACCCACCUUGGCUUCCCAAGGUGCUAGCAUUACAGGCAUGAGCCACCACGCCCAGCCUGUUCUAUUAAAAACAUCUUGACCUUUUUUUUUUUUUAAGUUUAUGAUAUAAAAACAGUCUGGUGGCUUUCCCUCAGGUUGGAUAUCUGAAGUUGUGGGAGCAGAUGUAGCUCCAUUUCCAUUUUAAUAUUAACUGGAUAAAUCCCACAUCUUCCCAGAACACAUCUGCUAAACACUUUAACAUGACAAGGAGCAAAUUACAAUUAUGUGUAAACUUAUAUCAUCCAGUACAAUGGCCCCUAGCCACAUGUGACUGAAAUUUAAAUUAGAAACUCAGUGCCUUCAGUCACACUAGCCACAUUUCAAGUGCUCAGCACCCACAUACGGCGUAGGACAAUGCUGGUCUAAAUUUUCACUCCAAAGAAUAAAACUUUGCCAUCAUGUUUAGGUCUUACAACUUUGAGUCCUAAAAGAUAAUAGGGAGAUGUGUGCUUAAAUUAAUUUACAAUGCUAAAUUAUAUUAGGUUAAACUGUAUGAAACCCUGCUAUUUGAUGAGUUCUGAUCUACAAAAAUGACAGCUCCACCUGAUCUGAUGUAUCACACAUUAACAUCACAUCUAAUUCAACCUGAAAUGUGAGUCUCCUUUGAUCUUGCAAAGUAUCUCCUAUGAAUCCGGGCUCUUUUGCUUAGAAGGUAGACAGCUGUAACCUCUAACAUUGAUACUUCGAUCUUCAGUCUCUCUGAAUGGGCAGCUGUUAAACAGUAAAGGCCUGGGCAGAGUUGAUGGUGAAAAAAAGCUGUAUUUUUAUACCAAAUGGAACUUCAGCAACACGUUGGACUACUUUGUCGGGCAGAGUGGUCUUCAGACAGGUGAUGCUGUUGGCUUAAGAGAUGAACACGUCUUCUCUCUGAAUUUGUUUUUAUUGGUUGGUUUUACUUGAACAGAAACGUUUGAAUGGUGUGAAGAUUCUUUAGAAAAGUGAUUGGAUCCAUCUCAAUUGUGCACUUGAACAGCAGUGAUGUAAAUGUGCUUAUUUGUGUUUUCAUUUUUAACUGUGCAGCCUUACCACACCUAUUUUGAAAGCUGAUCUUUUGUCCUCUUCAGGGCUUUUCCCUUGUGCCAUGUUGUCUCCAGCAAUAUAUGUGGCUUCUGGCUCAGAGCUUCUGCUGAGGCAGGGCCUCGCGCUGAGUCACAUGGCUCCUUGGAACAAGAAAACUUUCUCAGAAGUCCCCACACGGGUGGGUGACAGAAACAGUUUGUGGCAACACAAAUCUCUCUCCAUGGUGGAGAAACCUUUGCUUAUCCACUGUAUUCUACUCAGUGUAUAGUGAUGACAGAUGUACUAGAAUUAAACCAGUCAAGUGUACUGGCCCGGGGUGAGUGUUAAAUGUGUAUCUCGCCUGUGGAACCUACUCAGCAGCUUGGUUUCUGGGGUUGGGGGCAUAUUUAUUUCUUAAAGCCAAACCUCUCCUUCAUUGGUUUAGUGUACAUAAGUCUAUUUAGAUACACUUAUCCCACUUUAAUCUCCACCAGCCCCUAAACUCUCUCCUGUACCCUCUGUUGCUGAAGUGGCCUCUUCACCUGGGCCCUGGAAAAGCCGAUGGAAAAAGUCUGUUCCUGCAGCCAAGGCCUGGGUCCCAGGUGACUAGGAGUAGCCAUAGGAAGGUGAGGAAGGAGAAGUGGGCAUGUGGUGUCAUCUGUAGUCCAAGGUCUCUGCGUCUCGUCAGUGGGUGCAGUGCCUUCCCCCUCAGGUGUGAGCGUGAUGGACUCUAGACUGCCUUCCAUGAGUGUUGGUCAUGCUAUGAUGUCAUCAUUUGCCAUUAAAACCCAGUUUGUAUGAUGCCAAGAGGAUUAAUUGUGCAAGUGACUGAUUCAUUUAAAUUGUAAUCACAUCCCUUUUCUGCUUCACCAACCUGAACUGUUUUUAAAAAUAUCAUUAAAAGUCUGUUCUCUUUC